ACUUCGGUCCUGAGCGCUUGGGAGUUAGGUUGUUUGCCGGCGUAGCGGCCAGCGCCUGAGCCCGCCCUUGAUCUUCGCUGUGGCAUGGCGGACGAGGGGAAGUCGUACAGCGAACACGAUGAUGAACGCGUUAAUUUCCCUCAAAGAAAGAAGAAAGGCCGGGGUCCCUUCCGGUGGAAAUAUGGUGAAGGAAACCGUAGGUCUGGAAGAGGCGGUUCUGGUAUUCGGUCUUCCCGCCUUGAGGAAGAUGAUGGAGAUGUGGCAAUGAGUGAUGCCCAGGAUGGUCCCCGAGUACGAUACAACCCCUAUACCACCCGACCUAACCGUCGGGGUGAUACUUGGCAUGAUCGAGAUCGCAUUCAUGUUACUGUGCGGAGAGACAGAGCUCCUCCAGAGAGAGGAGGGGCUGGCACCAGCCAGGAUGGGACCUCAAAGAACUGGUUCAAGAUUACAAUUCCUUAUGGCAGAAAGUAUGACAAGGCAUGGCUCCUGAGCAUGAUUCAGAGCAAGUGCAGUGUGCCCUUCACCCCUAUUGAGUUUCACUAUGAGAAUACACGGGCCCAGUUCUUCGUUGAAGACGCCAGUACUGCCUCUGCAUUGAAGGCUGUCAACUAUAAGAUUUUGGAUCGGGAGAACCGAAGGAUAUCUAUCAUCAUCAACUCUUCUGCUCCACCCCACACUAUACUGAAUGAACUGAAGCCAGAACAAGUAGAACAGCUAAAGCUGAUCAUGAGCAAACGAUACGAUGGCUCCCAACAAGCCCUUGACCUCAAAGGCCUCCGUUCAGACCCAGAUUUGGUGGCCCAGAACAUUGACGUUGUCCUGAAUCGCAGAAGCUGUAUGGCAGCUACCCUGAGGAUCAUUGAAGAGAACAUCCCUGAGCUAUUGUCCUUGAACUUGAGCAACAACAGGCUGUACAGGCUGGAUGACAUGUCUAGCAUUGUUCAGAAGGCACCCAACCUGAAGAUCCUAAACCUUUCUGGAAAUGAAUUGAAGUCUGAGCGGGAAUUGGACAAGAUAAAGGGGCUGAAGCUAGAAGAGCUCUGGCUCGAUGGAAACUCCCUGUGUGACACCUUCCGAGACCAGUCCACCUACAUCAGGUCAGUUGUAGCCUGUGUCUCCCCUCCUGGGGACCUUCACCCCCUGGGAGGCUGAGCUAAUGCAUCCUGACCAGGGCCCGUCUGCGGAGAUGUGCAGCCCUGAGCUGGAACCACCUGUCCUUUGAGAGGAUCGCGUGCUCCCCACUUUGGUCUGUCUGUGUCUUCCAGCUUUGUCCUGAGAUGUUCUCUCUUCUCUUCUGACUUGACUAUCUGUUUGCUGGGUCUGUGGCCUUUCUCUUUCUUCCUGAACACAACCUUUUCUAGAAUCUCCCUACCCUGUUGUUCCAGGAAAGGCAUCUCCCCUUUCUACUCUAACCAGAGGGUAUCUUGUACAUACCCUAUAGAUGGGGUUGCCUUGUGCCAAGAGCCUGGUGUCCAUGGGUUGAGGAAGCCCUCCCUACCUGGGACUUCCUACUGAGAUGGGCCUUCCCUCCUUUGUACUGUGAUGGCCCCUCUUGCCCUUGCGCCAAGAGGGACCCUUUUCUCAGGAUCCACUUGCCCAGGGCUGUUGCUGUCCAUGCUGAGGUUGAGGCCUCCUAGGGGCUGGUGGCAUGCAAUCUGUCUCUCUUGCCCAGUGCUAUGAGCUGGGCUCUCCCUGAAGAAGAAACCUGGGUUCCCCAAGAUGUGACCAGAGCUGGGGCCCCGCCAGCAGGCGAGGGAAUCCCAAGGCAGGUGCUGGGCGUGGAGGCCACGGGGGCAUAGGCUACCAAGGAGACAGAGAACUGACCCCCUCGGGGGCGCUGCCUCUCCCUCACUCACACACUGCACGUCACCCUGUUUGGCCCCGGUGGAUGGCUGGUUAGCCAGAGACGGGUAAGAUUCCUCAGGGAAGGAACAACCUAAGACAGGCACAGUCGCAGAGGGGCCAUCAGGAGAGAACUUGGGGGCAACAGAGGUGGGGCAUGGACCCUCACCCCCACAAUCCUACAGGGGCCUGAACCCUCACACCUUCUGAGGGAGGUCUCCUGCCCCCAUGGCUGCUUUGCUUCCCACGCCCAGUUCAGAUCGGGACCCAGGUAGCAGACAGAGACCUGGCCAACAGCAAGUGCCCACUCACCACAGCAAGGAUUUGUUUCUCAUUUCUACCUUGGACCACAGGGAUGGGGCAGCUGAAAGAAAGGGCUGUGUCAGGGUGUCUUUCUCCCUUUUCUCCCUCAUUUUUCUAGAUGCUUUUUUGCCUUGUAGUUCUUUCUCUUUUUCUUUGCUUUCUCUUUCCUUUUUCUGUCUGUCUCCUAUACCUCCCCAUCUCUCCCUUGCCCCUGCCCCAUCUUGCCUUUUUCUCUUUUUCCUCCUUUUCCUUUCUUAUUCCUUUGCCUCUCCUCUUCCUGAGCCCCACCUGCUCAUCUCCCUGCCCCAACAUCCUGUGCCAUCCCUGUGGUGUGUUUGGGUCUUGGCCAAAGCCAGACCUGGCAGAACUGAUGGAUACCUGGUGAGGCAGCGGAGCCCCUGGGCUCCCACCCCAUUCCCUCCUCCCGGGGCUGCACAGGUGAGUAGGUGGAAGGUAAGGGGGGCAGGGAGGGGAAAGAGGUCCUGGGCUUAAAGCCUGGGCUUGGAGUACUGCUCCUUGACACUCAGGGUCAGGCAGAGAGAAAAGAGACAGCCUUCAAGGCAGUCCAUGUCUGGGUGCCCCGGGUCAGGUGGGGAGUGGGGGCCAUUUUUCCCUGAGCACAGGCUGGGAGGGAGUGGAGGGAUGAGCAGGAUGGGAUGGGCUGUCCCUCGGGUUUGGUAUAUUUGCUCCUAGAGCAGCCCAGGAGGCACGGUGGCUCUGAAGCAUCACUCACUUCUGUCCCGUUCUUGACAGCGCCAUUCGCGAACGAUUUCCCAAGUUACUACGCCUGGAUGGCCAUGAGCUACCCCCACCAAUUGCCUUUGAUGUUGAAGCCCCCACGACGUUACCGCCCUGCAAGGGAAGCUAUUUUGGAACAGAAAACUUGAAGAGUCUGGUCUUGCACUUCCUGCAACAGUACUAUGCAAUUUACGACUCUGGAGACCGACAAGGGCUCCUGGAUGCCUACCAUGAUGGGGCCUGCUGUUCCCUGAGCAUUCCUUUCAUUCCUCAGAACCCUGCCCGAAGCAGCUUAGCCGAGUAUUUCAAGGAUAGCAGAAAUGUGAAGAAGCUUAAAGACCCUACCUUGCGGUUCCGGCUGCUGAAGCACACGCGUCUCAACGUUGUUGCCUUCCUCAAUGAGUUGCCCAAAACCCAGCACGACGUCAAUUCCUUCGUGGUAGACAUAAGCGCCCAGACAAGCACAUUGCUGUGUUUUUCUGUCAAUGGAGUCUUCAAGGAAGUGGACGGAAAGUCCCGGGAUUCUUUGCGAGCCUUCACCCGGACAUUCAUUGCUGUUCCUGCUAGCAAUUCAGGGCUAUGUAUUGUAAAUGAUGAGCUAUUUGUGCGGAAUGCCAGUUCUGAAGAGAUCCAAAGAGCCUUCGCUAUGCCUGCACCCACGCCUUCCUCCAGCCCGGUGCCCACCCUCUCUCCAGAGCAGCAGGAAAUGUUGCAAGCAUUCUCUACCCAGUCUGGCAUGAACCUCGAGUGGUCCCAGAAGUGCCUUCAGGACAACAACUGGGACUACACCAGAUCUGCCCAGGCCUUCACUCAUCUCAAGGCCAAGGGCGAGAUCCCAGAAGUGGCAUUCAUGAAGUGAUCGUAGUCAUGCCUCAGAAGCAGUCCCCCCUGUAAAUAGUCCUUGGAUAUUACCGUCUGGUUGUCGUCUGUCAUCUCCUCCUGUCUGGCCCGAGGCCGCCCCGUGACUGUGACCGAGGGAGGGAGGGCUGCCUGAUCCCUCUCCUCGCCUGCCUUCUGGAAGACUUCAGAAGAUUGAGCCUCACUGGUGCCAGGAAGCCAAAGCUUACUUUGUAGAACUGACACUAAACUACCCGAAGGACUUAGGUGCUUUGUGUACUUAACCCCAGGACCUCCUUACUUUUUAAUAUAAAGAGUGAUGUUGUAUUUCGUGUUCUGCACUUUUUAAUAUAAAGAGUGAUGUUGUA